GGCGACGGCGACUGGCGGGUGGGAGUGGAGGCACCGGCUGGCGGGCGGGGGUACAGGGACGGGGCAGGGGCUCCCGCUCCAGGUUCCUUGAAGCACUUCCGACCGCGAAGCCCGGCGCGAGAAGCGAGCUAACCCAAGAGCCAACAACGAGCGCGGAGAGGGCAGCGGACUGAGCGGAGCCGCCGGCCAGAGCGGGCUCGGAGCCCGGGUCUCCGCCGCUCGGGACCCGGCUAGGCGGCGGCGGGGGCGGCGAUGUUCCACUGCAUCCCCCUGUGGCGGUGCAACCGUCAUGUGGAGAGCAUCGACAAGCGCCACUGCUCGCUGGUCUACGUCCCCGAGGAGAUCUACCGCUAUGCCCGGAGCCUGGAGGAGCUGCUGCUGGACGCCAACCAGCUCCGCGAGCUGCCCGAGCAAUUUUUCCAGCUAGUCAAAUUACGAAAGCUUGGACUUAGUGAUAAUGAAAUUCAGCGGCUCCCUCCAGAAAUAGCAAACUUCAUGCAGCUGGUGGAACUAGAUGUGUCUCGAAAUGAGAUUCCUGAAAUUCCAGAAAGCAUUUCAUUCUGUAAAGCACUGCAGGUAGCUGACUUCAGCGGAAACCCACUGACUAGGUUGCCAGAAAGCUUUCCUGAAUUACAGAAUUUAACAUGUCUUUCUGUAAAUGACAUCUCACUACAGUCUCUACCUGAAAAUAUUGGCAAUCUUUAUAACCUGGCUUCACUGGAACUGAGAGAGAAUCUUCUUACAUAUCUUCCUGACUCUCUUACCCAGCUGCGAAGACUAGAAGAACUUGAUUUAGGAAACAAUGAAAUAUAUAAUUUGCCAGAAUCAAUUGGAGCCCUCUUACAUCUAAAAGAUCUCUGGUUGGAUGGAAAUCAACUGUCAGAAUUACCUCAGGAAAUAGGAAAUCUGAAGAACCUGCUGUGUUUAGAUGUCUCUGAAAACAGGUUGGAAAGACUUCCUGAAGAAAUCAGUGGCCUGACUUCAUUAACGGAUUUAGUCAUUUCCCAGAACUUAUUAGAAACGAUUCCGGAUGGCAUUGGAAAACUAAAGAAACUGUCAAUCUUGAAGGUGGAUCAGAAUAGACUCACACAGUUGCCUGAAGCAGUUGGGGAAUGUGAAAGUCUCACUGAGUUAGUUCUUACAGAAAAUCAGCUCCUGACCCUGCCUAAAAGCAUUGGAAAACUAAAGAAGUUGAGCAACUUGAAUGCAGACAGAAAUAAAUUAGUGUCCUUACCAAAAGAGCAAUAAAGCCUAAAACUAGCUGUUGAUGAGCCUUCUCCUUUGCUGGGUCCUCAUCUGGAAAGGUAUGGUAUUUCCUUGGAUGAUAUGAUCACUGGCUGGGUGUAGUUUGCUUCAUAUUUCUGUUUUGACUUUUUCUAACGUCUAUUUUGGUGUAAUUUCAAAGCUGCCUUCCAGCCAGUCAGAACAUGUGGCGUUCUUGUUUUCCUAGGGCCACAUCUCAGGGUAUCUGAACUUCCUCUUUCCUUUCCUCAUCUUGGUGUUCGGCCCACAGUGUCCCAGUCUUCUCCCUGGGUAAGGUGGCCAGCAUUUCUAAAUGGAGACAUGAGAAUAUUUACUAUAAACAUGAUCAUAUUCUGAAACAUCCUUAAUAUGAACACUGUCAUCUAAGUAAACUGUUUCUGGCUGUAAGACUUCAGUCUGUUUCUCAGCAAAACUGGGACUCAACUAAGAGAUUCUACUAAUUAGAAAAGUUGGCUUCUAGUUUCUAAGCAAUAAACCAAAAUACAGAACUGAUAUUCUGAACAGUUGAAUUUACUCUUGCUGAAUAGUGCUUGCAGAUGGAUAGUAGAUUGGGCAUAUAAACACACAUACAGAUGUAGAAAAUAUUUCUUUCUUUCUUUUUUAAUGCCAGGCACUGUACUAGAUGCUUUCAAGUAUUUGUUGUACUUGUUGAAUCCUUACAACAGCUUUUGCAGUCAUGAUAAUUUCUUCAUUUUACGAGUGAGGAAACGGAGGCCAGUAAGUAGUUUUUCUUACUAGGGCUCACACAGCUGGGAGUUGGUAGAACCUGACUCCAAAGAUGAGUCUCCCAGUAAACACGUGACCACUUAUGUAAUGCAGGCUCAGCCCAACCUUUCCAUCUGUGUGACCUUGAGGUAGGGCAAGCCCCUGAUUUGUUAAGGAAAAGCCAAAGUAUCUUUAGUUUGGACACUACAGAAAAUUAACACAUUUUAGGUGUUCUUUCAAGGCAGAUCAUGAGGAGAGCACUUUUAGGUGUAAUGUUAAUUCCCAGCAAGUUUCACCACCCAUCCCCAGCUUCCCUGAUCCCCUGACUCUCUUUCACAAGAUUAUGUUCUAGACAAGAACCUUGGAAAUUUACUUUCAUAAAACUUUCACCAUCAUUUCAGCAUCGGUCCUCUUUUUCACUUUAAAAGAAUGAAACACACUCAAGAGUUUCUGACUAGAGGGUUAUAUCUAGUCCAUGCUAUGUGUUCACUAAAUUUACUAGAACAGUUUUUCAUGACGUGAAAAGUGAAAAUAUGAAAGUAUUUCUAACUUCAAAGCGUUUUAGUCAUAUUUUGUCCAUUUUCUGAGAAAUUAUGAUUGGUUUUCUGGCUUCUGGCAUUUUAGAAAGAAAUAGUCUGCGCCUUUCCUUUCAGCUGUCUGAUAAAGCAGAGAAUGUUUAGGUUUUUAGGAGUUGGAUCUUUUCUAGAUCACCUCCUACUUACAUACACUCAGCUCCCAGCGUAGGAAAAUGUGCUGAGCACAUGUCUCCAAUUCUCCCUCGGAUCACAGUUUGCUGCCUAGCAGAAAUGGUUGAGUGCUUGCCUCUGACCAUCAGGGCUGAGCAGCCAAACCAGCAAGAGCCUCCUGACCUCUCAUUGCAUCACGUUGGCCCAGGCAGCACUGUCAUGUCAUGAGUCUCUGUGCAGUGAGUGUGGUAGGCCCUGUGACUGUGUGUAUGUUAGCUCUGCCUCCAAGCUUGAUGCCAUUUGAUCAAAUCUUGCAUUUUCCUGAUUGGAUUCUUCCAAAAAUAUAUUGCUUUCUCUUGAACAGUUAAGUUGCAUACAUAUCUAAACUGAAAUGCUGACCGAUUCAAUUCAUAUGCCAAAAAUCCAUAGUAGUAUUAAUUGCCAUUGGUCUGGUAUGCUGUGUAGUUCUUCCUAUAUUUUUUCCUUUAAAAAAAACAACAACAUUUAUAGUAUUGUGUGUUGCCAGUUUUAGGGCACAGCUCCUUAGUCUGUAGCAGCAUUUAUUUGCAUUUUUUCCCCAAAUGGUUGAGGGGAAGAUGUUUGUACCAUGUGGGUCACAAUAUGGAUUCUGUUUGUGUUUUGUGGUGUUAUUUGUAGUAAACAUUUGCAAAUCAAUGAAUGUCUUUUGUUUUCUUAAUUGUUAGCUGCUUGGAAAUUUAGAAAAGUCAGGUAAACUUGUUAUCUUGUAAGUAUUGUUCAGACCACAGUUGCAUCUCUAACUUCCAUUCUGCUUCUUAAAUGCAUGAAGAUUCACAUUGGCUGACUGCUUUGUGUGCUCUUCAUUGUAAAAUAUUGGACAUUUUCUUCUAAAUUCAUUUUUUUUUUUUUUUUAAUGACUGCAUGGCCUGGAACCUUACUUUGUUAUGUGUUUUUCAAGUUUGUUCAGAUUAUUCACUCUCAAAAGAAUGCUUUUCUGUGAAUUACAUUUUAAGUUAUUCAGAAAUCCUGAAAGGCAUCAUUUGGCAGCUCAUCUGUUUUCACUAAAUUGUAAGUUUGUCGGCACAAAUCUGUCUCUAAUGGAAAGGCUAGAUUUGCUUUAUUUGCUACACCUGGCAUGCCUCUGAUUUUUCAAGUCACUUAUUUGUGUCUUUUAUUUUUCAUCCUGUUGCUUAAGUAUAUAUACUUCUGGGAAAAGAUUUCUUAAAAACUCAUAGUGUUGGUGGAGAGGAGAGUUAAGGAACAUAUUGUGCAGUAGUAUGAUUGAUUCAUGGAUAGAUGGAGUUGGUGGUAUAUGUGUGAGCAUGAGUAUGAUGAAUGAGAGCCAGACCAUAAAGAGUUUUUGGCUAGAAGAAAUUGAGCUUAUAUCCAAGUUUAGGGUCCUGUUUUCUUUUUGUCUCCAUUAAGUCCAAAUGAAAGAGACGCCAACUAAGCCACACUUACCCAGUCAGAUGAGGCAACAUAGCAUUUGCAGAUCAUUCAUCAAAGCUUUUUUCAGUCAGGCAACCUGUAAAUAUUAAUUACCCAUAAAUAUUACUAUGAUACUCAGAAAUGCCUGUGGUGAUAGAAUAUUCAUUUUGUGGAUAGUUUUUCUGCCUUCUUAUUAUUGCAAUUCAAAAUUCUUUCAGUAUAAGUUUCCGUUGUAUUCUAAAAUGAAUUAUUGAUUAAAGACAUGAUAUAGAAUAUAAAAAUAUUAGAUAAAAUAUAGUUGACCAUCAAAUUUCAAGAUGGAGAAGUAAUUCCUAAACUUGAAAUAAGUCAUAAAAAAUAGUUGAUGGAUUGUCUACAGGAAAAUUCGAUUUCUGAUCUUCAAGAAGGUAAAAGCAGCCUUUACUUUCUUGAAAGGGGGCAGGGAGACAUUUAAGGCAUCUUAAAUGAGAGAUCUGUCUUUACUCUAUUAGAAGUUCUUCUACACCAAUAAGGAAAAGAUGUAUUUACUAUAGAGAAGUAGACAAAAAGAAACUUCCACAAAAACCAGCAAGUGAUUCACACAAGAACAAAUAGAAAUGGCAACUAAUGUGAAACAAUUUCAGCCUCAUCAGUAUUCACAAAAAAAUUUAAUAAUGCCAAAUUUUGGCAAGGGUGGAGGGAAAUAUAUAUUAUCAUGUAAAUAUAAAUUAUUAUGACUUUCUGGAAGGGAAUAUGAUAAUAGUAAAAACUUUAGAAAUGUGCGUACCCUUUGAUUCUGCAAUUCCACGUCUAGGAAAACAUUUAUGGAUAUACACUAAGAAUGAUGUACAAGAACAUUUCUCACAUUAUACAUGGGAGCAGGCACCAUACCAAGUGUCCACAGAGGCAGCUAACAUGUGCCAGGCAUGGUGCCAAGGGCUUUUGCACUUAUUCUUAUCUAAUUAUCACAACAGUUCUAUGAGGUAUAGGUAAACCAUUUUCAAUGUCCAACAGAUUGUGAAACUAAGACUGAGAGAGGUUAAGUCACUUGUCCAGAGUCACACAGCAAAGAAGUGGCAGACCUAACUAGCAUUGUCUAACCUGGGCAGUUUCUUAAAUAAUCUGUGAUACAUCCAUAGAAGGAAAUAACUAUGUGGUCCAUAAAAGUCCUCUUAGAAGCAUUGUUAAAGUGUGUAUGUAUAAUCACAAAUGCAAGGCAGUGGUACUGGAAGAUUGUACCUCAUAAUGUUAAUACUGAUUAUCCCUUUGUGGUAAGAUUUGAUUUUUUUUCAUUGUGCUUUCCUGUGCAUGUAUGUUUAGUUUUUAUUUUUCUAAUCAAUGUAAGGUACUUUUUUAUAAUCAGAAAAAAAAAAAAGAAUUCCGUAGCUAUUAGUGGAUAUUUUGAUGUCAGUGGCCUCAGAAUUCAGGGAAUCCCAAAGCCACACAAUUGCCAAAAAUAUUUAUGAAGUAGGGAACAUUUGAAUAAUAUGCCAUAGAUGAUGGGAUUCUAAAAUUAUGCUUCAUAUUAUUUUUGUUCAAAUUGCGUUUUGGCCAGAUUUUACUUAUUGUACACUUUUCUUUUUUUGCCAAUGGGGUGUGUGUUCAAUUAUGUUACAAAUAAUAUUAAAAGGAAUAUACUGAAGGAAAGUGAAAGUUCCCUUAUACUUAAGGCAAGCAUUUAAAAAAUGGAAGAUAAACAGACGUGACUAACAUAGGCUCCCUUUUUGAAUCACUGAAUCUGUCUCAUGAUCUCCUCCUUGGGUGAGCUAACCUGCAGGCAAUUAAUACCUAGUGAAAGUUGACCUGAGCAGAGGUUUGCUCAAUAAUCUGCAGAACCUAUUUUCUUGAGAUGGGUUAAAUCAGUGCAUAACAGCUAAGGAGAGUAUCAUUUUGAAUUAAGAGAGACACAAAAUGGCUGGACAAAGAUUCUCAGCUAUAUUCCAUAAUUCUCAGAGAAUCCAAGUCCAACCCCUUGUAUUCUGGGAAGGUGCUAUUAUGUGGUUUAAGGGAAGCUUAAAAAUAUCAGCUUCCUACAUAACUGGUAAUAAGUUAUUUAAACAGUGACUCUGCUUCCCAGAACUUCUAAGUGAUACAUUUUAUCCUGAUUACCACUGAGAAACCUGUAAACUCUGCCUCCUGAACCCAAAAGAGAAAGCCAAAAUAUAUAUGAAUGAUGUGUAUAAUGUCAGUCUUCAUUAUUAUUAAUACAAAAUGUCACUGCGAUACAUCGUUAGGGAGAUGGGUUUUUUAAGACAUUCGGGUAAGUUCAGGAAAGAGACUGCCAGCAUCAGUACAGUUCUAAGAACAUAGUAGGUAUUCAGGUGUUGAUUGUACUCAUCAUUUGGAUCUGAGGUUUUUAUUUCCUGGAAAAAAAAAUAGCUACCACAUUUAUUUGGCAACAGCAAAAGGCCAGUUUCUAUGAUAGGCGCCAAAUUAUAUAUGUGGUUUCAUUUAAGUUAAUCAUUAUUGUUACUUUUGGUUAAAGUAACAUAUCCAAAACCACAAAACAUAUGACUGAGCCUAAAUUCUAGCCCAGGUCUGUAUGGUCUCAAAGCAUCCGCUCCCUCCAUCAUACCGCAUCUCCCUCUGACGUCUAUAAUGAACUAUAUCUUUUCAGUUAUGGGUUUGAAUGCUUAAUAAUCUUUUCUAAAAACCAAAGGUUGUGCCAUCCCUUCCUGGCUGAUUUGGAAAGAGGGCUGUGUUUAUGUGAAUGUUCGCUGGGACAGCAUGUGCCUUUGUGGGGUGAUUAAGGCAUCCCUAGCACACUCUGCAACAACAUGUGCUCUUUGUUGGCAUUGUUUUUCAUAAACCAUAGACAAUAGAGAUCAGGAGGUCACACUGCCUGCUUUGACAACCCAGAGGGCCUAAGAGGCUCUUGUACGCAAUUGCUUUCCACCCCUUGACGUCUCAAAUGGGUGUGAGAUUAGAGUGGGAAAGGAAAAAGAAAAAUGAAACAAUAACACACAGUAGACAGCUCACACACUUCAUUGAAGUUUACACAAUAUGUUCCCAAAUGAUUAAUGGAUCUUGUCCAGAACAUUUAUUUAGAGCCUUCUCUGACCCACUUUAAUUAAUUAAUUUUUUUGACUACAUAAUAUAUGCAUAUGAUACAAAUUGAAAAUGUUCACAUGGUAUAGCAGUAGGGCCCCAAAACAGAUAUCUUACAGGUUGGUGUGGUGGGAGGGCAGUGGACAGCUUCAAGACAAGAUGCCCAGAAUUAAAAUGCAGUCCCAGCUCUGUAUGUCUUCCAGGAGCUGAUUAUCCCAUCCGGACGAUCAUAUGAAUGAUAAUAUCUGCUUUGCCCCCCUUGGGUCACACAUAAAUCCUGUCUCUUCAAAGCUAGAUCAGGACGCUAGCGGGGGUCUUCAGCCUCAGCCAACUGCUGACUUGGAAGCUCUCCUUCAGGGCAUGCAGCCGUACCUCUGAACCCCAGCCUGACACCGAAGCUCCUCCACCUGGAGCAGGGAUGCGGCAAGGGUGCCCCAUGGGAACCUAGUCAUUCUUUCUCAUGAGUAGAUCUUUGUCAGGAUUGUCUAAAUUUAUCAGAGACUCUAAUAAUAUUGAUCAUCAAAAGGAUCAGGGUUUUGAUUGCUUUCCUUCCAUGAUAUUUCUGGGCACCUAGGUAGAAUUGUUGAUUCCCUUCCUCAAGGGAGGGAGAAUAUGCUCAGCCAUAUGGGAAAUCCACACUAUAUUGGGGCUUGAUGUUUCUAAAACCUAAGAAAGGCUACUCUGGUGAUUCUUACUGGAACAAAAAAGAGUUUUGUUGUCUCCACUGCUACACAUAGAGGCAGAUAACUUUUAAGUAGAGGUCUUUCACAAGUAAGUAAAUAAAGUGUAUAAACAUAUGUAAA